ACAGAGCCGUCCCCGCCCGCCCGCGCCCCGACCAGCCCGGCCUCGGGCAGCCACUCACCGGUGUCCCCGUCCGCGUCCUUUCUCCCCGGGUCCCGGCCAUGGCGCUGAGUGAACCCAUCCUGCCGUCCUUCUCCACUUUCGCCAGCCCGUGCCGCGAGCGCGGCCUGCAGGAGCGCUGGCCGCGCGCCGAACCCGAGUCCGGCGGCACCGACGACGACCUCAACAGCGUGCUGGACUUCAUCCUGUCCAUGGGGCUGGAUGGCCUGGGCGCCGAGGCCGCCCCGGAGCCGCCGCCGCCGCCCCCGCCGCCUGCGUUCUAUUACCCCGAACCCGGCGCGCCCCCGCCCUACAGCGCCCCCGCGGGUGGCCUGGUGUCUGAGCUGCUGCGACCCGAGCUGGAUGCGCCGCUGGGGCCCGCACUGCACGGCCGCUUUCUGCUGGCGCCGCCCGGCCGCCUGGUCAAGGCCGAGCCCCCUGAAGCGGACGGCGGCGGCGGCUACGGCUGCGCCCCCGGGCUGACCCGUGGACCGCGCGGCCUCAAGCGCGAGGGCGCCCCGGGCCCGGCGGCUUCGUGCAUGCGAGGUCCCGGGGGCCGCCCCCCGCCGCCGCCCGACACACCGCCGCUCAGCCCCGACGGCCCCGCGCGCCUGCCCGCGCCCGGUCCGCGCGCCUCCUUCCCGCCGCCUUUCGGUGGCCCUGGUUUCGGCGCGCCCGGGCCCGGCCUGCAUUACGCGCCGCCUGCGCCCCCAGCCUUCGGUCUCUUCGACGACGCGGCCGCCGCCGCGGCAGCCCUGGGCCUGGCGCCCCCCGCCGCCCGCGGUCUCCUCACGCCGCCUGCGUCCCCGCUGGAGCUGCUGGAGGCCAAGCCAAAGCGCGGCCGCCGCUCUUGGCCCCGCAAACGCACCGCCACUCACACCUGCAGCUACGCGGGCUGCGGCAAGACCUACACCAAGAGUUCGCAUCUGAAGGCGCAUCUGCGCACGCACACAGGUGAGAAGCCCUACCACUGCAACUGGGACGGCUGCGGCUGGAAGUUUGCGCGCUCAGACGAGCUCACGCGCCACUACCGAAAGCACACGGGCCACCGGCCAUUCCAGUGCCAUCUGUGCGAUCGUGCCUUCUCGCGCUCCGAUCACCUGGCGCUGCACAUGAAACGGCACAUGUAGCCGGGACGCCCCCGCCCACCUGCGCGCGGCCGUGGCGGGUCCCACGCGCCGGGCGCGGCCCCCUCCCAAACUGUGACUGGUAUUUAUUGGACCCAGAGAACCGGGCCGGGCACAGCGUGGCUACAGAGGGUCUCCCUCGAUGACGACGACGACGACGCCACCACCCCAGCCCCCGUCUGUGACUGAAGGCCCGGUGGGAAAAGACCACGAUCCUCCUUGACGAGUUUUGUUUUUCAAAAUGGUGCAAUAAUUUAAGUGGCAUCUUCUCUCCCACCGGGUCUACACUAGAGGAUCGAGGCUUGUGAUGCCUUGUGAGAAAUAAGGGCCUUAAUUUGUACUGUCUGCGGCAUUUUUUAUAAUAUUGUAUAUAGUGACUGACAAAUAUUGUAUUACUGUACAUAGAGAGACAGGUGGGCAUUUUUGGGCUACCUGGUUCGUUUUUAUAAGAUUUUGCUGGGUUGGUUUUUUUUUUAAUUAAAAAGUUUUGCAUCUUUUAAAAAAAAUCACAGCACUGGUCUGGUUGCUUGGAACUGGGGCCUUGGGGCACUUGGGAGGAGGGGGGAGCGGAGAGUUUGAUGGAGGGCAGCCCCACUAAAGCAUCGUGUGCAGUGGGUCCUGCGUCUGCCAGCACCGGGACUGCCAGCUGCUGUGCCUGCCUGCCAGGAACCUGUGGGUUUUUCUGUAAAUUUAGACACUGCAUUUUAGGACUGAGGGAGGGUUAUUUUAAGGUUGUUCUUUGAGCCAUAAAUUGCCUCUUUGCCCCACAGCUGGGGAAAGUGCUGGUCCCACUGACGUGGCCUCCUCUACGUUGAAAAAAAUAAAACUACUUACCUCUUCCUGGAAGCCUCUGAGGUUUUAGCCAAAUUUCUGGAGUGCCAGCUCUAUAUUUUUAUUUUUAUUUUUAAAGGGGGUUAACCUGCUGAGUUUCUGGCAUGUUCUGCCCUUUACUCGUCUCGACAUUUAGCAAGUCUUUUCUUAAGGGGUGAGUUCCCCAUUCUGCUAGCGGAAAACAGUGAAACCUGCAUUCGAGGGCCAUGCAUGAAGCUCUUUUCCAGAUGAGGAAACGGAGGCCCGGAGAGGUAGCGGCAGGGUGGUGGAGUUGGGUUGUUAGCCUGCUCUGUCUGCCUCCAAGGGUCCCUGAACCCCACUGGAAGGGAGUGGUAGCUUUCUACAAUGACCCACCUGUUGUGUGCAUUGGAAGGCUAGGAGAGCCUCCUCCCCUGUAGGUCUCCUGGUGCAAAAAAUUCACUGCCUCAAUGGUAGGAGGUGACCAGUCUGGAAACCCACCUGGAGAGCAGAGGAGACCCCUAAAUCCCACCACCCCAAGUGUCUCAGGCAAGGAGGUAUCUCUCCCCCCAGAUUUCACCUGCCACCCCUCACCUUCCCCAUUCUCAGGGGCCCCGGGUAACCAUGACCACCAACCAUUGCACAAGUUUCCAGAAAGUGAAAAUAGCUCGUAAGCAGCGCCUGCUUUAAAACACUCUCACCCCGUUGCGACAGAGGCUGGGAUUUCCUCCCUCCCUGCAUCCUUCCUCCUCCCCAACUACGGCAGCCCUGGAAACAGCUGAGAGGUGUUUGGUAAUCCACGAAAAGCAGAAAUACGAUUUGACAAUCUGAUUCAUUUUCCGAGAGUAAAUAGCCUGGCCUCACUUCC